GAGUUCCACAUCUGAUACCCAGGAGUCUCCAGCUUCCAAGAGAGGUCGGGUCACAGCCAGCAGCUAUGUCUGACAUAAAUCUUGACUGGGUUGACAGGCGUCAGUUGCAGCGCUUGGAGGAAAUGCUGAUUGUUGUGGAUGAGAAUGAUAAGGUUAUUGGUGCCGACACCAAGAGGAAUUGCCAUCUGAACGAAAACAUUGAGAAAGGGCUGCUGCACCGAGCCUUCAGCGUUGUCUUGUUUAACACCAAGAAUCGAAUCCUGAUACAGCAGAGGUCGGACACGAAAGUCACGUUUCCUGGGUAUUUUACCGACUCCUGUAGUAGCCACCCAUUAUACAACCCAGCAGAACUGGAAGAAAAGGAUGCCAUCGGAGUGAGGAGGGCAGCCCAGAGGCGUCUGCAAGCAGAGCUGGGAAUUCCUGGGGAGCAGAUUUCUCCAGAGGACAUUGUGUUCAUGACAAUCUAUCACCACAAGGCAAAAUCAGACAGAAUUUGGGGAGAGCAUGAAAUUUGUUACCUUCUGCUUGUGAGGAAAAACGUCACUCUGAACCCGGAUCCCAGUGAAACGAAAAGCAUCCUCUACCUGUCCCAGGAGGAGCUGUGGGAGCUGCUGGAGAGGGAGGCGAGGGGUGAAGUCAAAGUCACCCCCUGGCUAAGAACCAUUGCCGAGAGGUUUCUGUACCGGUGGUGGCCUCACCUGGAUGACGUGACCCCGUUUGUGGAGCUUCACAAAAUACACAGAGUGUGAGAGGCAGGGAGGUCGAGUCAGCCAUGUGUAAUGCCCUCAGUGCAGGCAGACGCACCAUUGAGGCAAUGAUACACCCUCUCCAAAAAACAGGGCAAAAGGGGCACUUGAUUGCCCAUCAUGUAUAAAUCACUAUUUCAACCUUUUCAUCAACUUUGUCAUAUCUUCAUUUUCCCUUUUCCUUAUUUCCAUAUUUCUCAUCUGCCUGGUUGCAGGGAGGAAAUUUAACAUUUCCUUUGUCCCAAUUUCCAUUUUAUAAGCACUUGUUUGAUUAACAGCAGCUGAUCCUGAAAGUCUUGGGGAGAUCUUGAGAGUCCUGAAGCAGGCGGACUAGCCUGGCUGGACCAUGAGGCUGUCUCCCCACAGCUUUAUCCAAGCCUCCAAGGUCAGGAUGGGAUCUCUGUAUCAUGUUUUUCUUUUUAAAUCACUUAUUUCAGAGUGCAACACAAGGCUGCAUUUUUAAAAAAAAGACACAUUCAAUCUUGCAUCCUAAUACAAGCAGUACGGAAGAUGCGUAUGGUCUCAGCCAAGUGACUCGACGUUUAUCCACUUCUGUUCAUUUGAUCGUUUCAGUAAUAUGCUUACAAAUAAAGACAUACUUGCUUUAAAA